AUUCUUUAUCCGGAAUUUCAAGGGCCGCCGGAGGGCUGUCGCUUCUGCAGUGCGUAGGAGCGGCCGGGGCGGGAGGCUCCGCGGAGCCGAGGCGUGGAGAAUAAGAAAGCCUUGAGUUUUGUGAAAAACCGGAGAAGAGAAACUAAAAGGACAGUAGAAAAGGCUUUUCCAGUUUGCAUAAUAUUUCCUUCAUGGAUACUUUUUCAUAGCAUUAUUAUGUGAUGUGAGAAGUUUUUUUUUUUGAAGUAACAUGGAUUUUAUACUACAGAAUCAAGAGAAUUGGCUUAUAGGAAAAAUUGAUUUAUAAAAAGUGGUACAGGUUUUCAUAGAUAACCAUGACAACAUCCCAUAUGAAUGGGCAUGUUACAGAGGAAUCAGACAGCGAAGUAAAAAAUGUUGAUCUUGCAUCACCAGAGGAACAUCAGAAGCACCGAGAGAUGGCUGUUGACUGCCCUGGAGAUUUGGGCACCAGGAUGAUGCCAAUACGUCGAAGUGCACAGUUGGAGCGUAUUCGGCAACAACAGGAGGACAUGAGGCGUAGGAGAGAGGAAGAAGGGAAAAAGCAAGAACUUGACCUUAAUUCUUCCAUGAGACUUAAGAAACUAGCCCAAAUUCCUCCAAAGACCGGAAUAGAUAACCCUAUGUUUGAUACAGAGGAAGGAAUUGUCUUAGAAAGUCCUCAUUAUGCUGUGAAAAUAUUAGGUAAGUAAAAAUAGAGGUAUAACAGAAAACAUUUUGCUUUAAUUUAUCUGUGCCUUAUAAUGUAUAUGAGAAGGAAGAGGGUUUAAGAGAAUGUAAGUAAUGACAGUUUGAAUUCCAGACCAAGAUCCUUUGUUUUCGUGGAAACGCCGUAUAACUAUUGUUUACUGUUACCAACAUAGAGCUAAAAGCAUGUGGCUUAAAUGUUAAGUCACUAUAACAUGUUUUUUUAGAUAUUAAAGAGUUCUGCAUGGGCCCUAACAUUUAAAGCCUUGAAAUUUACCUUUUAUAUCAAACCACAAACUUUAUGCAAAAUACUAAAAAAGAAUUUUCAGAUUUUGAAUUUCUGAUUUCCUUAAAGUUUUGUAAAAUAGUAAUAAAUUUGUAACUACAGUUUAAAUUCUUUGAUUUUUUUAAAUUAAUGAUUGUCAAUAAAAAGAACUGGUAUUGUUCAUAUGGUAUCAUAAACUUAAAAUAAUGGUAUUUUCUAUAUCCCCAAAUUCUGUUCUGUGGGGGGAAAAAAAGUCCUAUGAGAUAUAAGUAGAUACAACCGAACCAAAAGAAUUCUGUGACCAAAUGGAUUUUGAGAACUCUGGGCUAAAUAAGUUAAAUAGCUUCUUAUCACGGGACUUCUCAUAGCUGUUAGAAUGUUACUAGGCAUUGUGAAUCUACAAGAGAGAUUGAUAUCAAAUGCAUGUUUCCAAACUUAGAAUAUUUAAUCAUUGAAUUUACUGCCUGCCCUUCUUGCACGUGCACAUACACCCAAGUGCUCACUGAACUAGUGUUAGGAGAGCAUUUUAUUUUUUGGUGGUUUGCUAUUUUUUAGGUGUGAAAAAAGAUAUAUUUCUACUUUUUUGUAGAAGGAGAAAGUUUUUAUUGUCAUUGUCAUCAUUUUGCCAUUCAUUUAAGGGUCUGUUUAGCCUGUACUAAGUGUUUUAGCAAACAUUGUUUCAUGUAAUAAAAUAAUCCUGUUAACAGUACUCUGUAAUCUCCAUUUUGGAGAUAAAGAAAUUGAACCUUAGUUAAACAACUUUUUAAAGACACCAAUGGUAGAGCCAAGUUUGAAUUUGCCAGAUCAGGUGUUGAUGUACUACACAAAAUGGUUUGAAUGGAAACCGGUAUCCAGCCUGCGUUUCACUCACCAGGCCAGAGCUGUGGCUACCCAGAAUAGAGCACCUUUUUCUAAUUUGGCCAAAGGUACCAUGUAUAUGCCAGAUUUGUUCCUCAUUAAGUCUCUUUAUUCCAACUCUGGAGCAGUUUCCUUCCUUCCUUCCUUCCUUCCUUCCUUCCUUCCUUCCUUCCUUCCUUCCUUCCUUCCUUCCCUCCCUCCCUCCCUCCCUCCCUCCCUUUUCUUUCUUUUCUUUCUUUCUUUUUUUUUUUGAGGUGGAGUCUUGCUCUGUUGCCCAGGCUGGAGUGCAGUGGUGCAAUCUUCGGCUCACAGCAAUCUCCGCCUUCCCAGGUUCAAGUGAUUCUCCUGCCUUAGCCUCCCGAGUGGCUGGGAUUACAGGCAUGUGCCACCACACCUGGCUAAUUUUUGUAUUUUUAGUAGAGACCGGGUUUCACCAUGUUGGUCAGGCUGGUCUUCAACUCCUGACCUCAUGAUCUGCCCUCCUUGACCUUCCAAAGUGCUGGGAUUACAGGUGUGAGCCACUGUGCCCGUCUCAAGUCUGGAGCAGUUUCUACUACAUCACAUCAUCUUCUUUUCUUUGUUAUAAAUUUUUAUUCAGGAUCCACAUUUCAUAUGUACAUGCUUUUCUGUGUUUUAAGAAAUCAUAGAUAUGUGUUCAGUCAUAGUGAAGUCUGCUAAAUUCCUGCCUUCAGACAUUUUAAUUACAGUGAAAGCUAAAAGAUUACAUUUUUUUAAUACCUUUAUGUGAAAGAAUUUUAUGCUCUUUUUUCCUGAGGGUUUUAUUAGAGUAAAAAUACUUCAUUCCUGAUUGCUUCUUACUAGCCUUCAUUUCCCACCACUCUAUUAUUAUUUAUUUAUUUAUUAAAAUAUUCUGAAAAUAUUUUAUUGGAGAAAGUUUGUUAUAUCCAGUGCAAACCUGGAUUGAUUCUUCUGUUUUUCUGUUUACAUUCCCUUAAGAUUAAAGUAUUUGUCCAUUUGGUUUACUUAGAAUCAGGUGUAAGUAUCCAUCUGAUAGGUAAUAUUCAUGUAAUCACAGUAAAGAAACAAAUAUAGCUUCAGCCGGAUUCACUUAGUAAGAGAACAGUUGUGAGUUUAUGGUUUUGUUUGUUUUGCCUAAGCACACAAAAUUGGACAUCAUUUCUCUUAAUUUUUUUUUUUUGCUUUUUCCUGUUUCUGUUUGAAUGUUCUAUUGCUGACUUUUUUACAAAUUCAGAUUAAAGGAUACCUCUAUUCCAAUGUGUAAUCUGCUGUGGUUUUUAAAAGUACCUAUGUGUGGUCCUUGAAUUUAAGGCAGUUUUGUGUAUUUUAUUUUAAAGUAAUUUGAAAUGUCAUAACAGGUAUUUGUAAUUCAUUUCUUGGAUAGGAGAAGAUGUAUUUUGAGAAAUAAAUGAUAUAUUUUAUGUUGAUAUAGUCAACACAGAUAUCUGUUAUGUAAGAAUCAUGAGAAAUUAGCAUAAGGUAUAGUUUGCUAUUGUCAGUCAUAGCCUCAGGUUUUUAACUUUUUGUUUAAAGUGAAGUGUAAUAGCUUUUUGCCAAACUUUUUUUUCUUGUUCAUAAUCUGCUAACACAUCAAACUGUAAGAGAAGUACUCCCUGAACAUUGUGUGUGUCUCCUGGCUAGUAUUUGAUUAAUACCCAUAUGACAGGAGACAACUUCUCAGCCUUUUUCACAUCUAGAAACAGCAACCUUAUUUUAAAUGAGGGAAGAAUGGGCAACUGAUUUAUUUCUCUGAGAGGAAGCCUUCAGUUUCUAAACAAUACAUCAUCAUUUAUCUAAAUAGAAGACUUGUUUUCUUCACUUAAACAUAUCCAACAUACUUUGGUAGAUUCUCAGAGCCAGGAGGAUAUUUCACUGCUUUUACAACUUGUUCAAAAUAAGGAUUUCCAGAAUGCAUUUAAGAUACACAAUGCCAUCACAGUACACAUGAACAAGGCCAGUCCUCCAUUUCCUCUUAUCUCCAACGCACAAGAUCUUGCUCAAGAGGUACAAACUGUUUUGAAGCCAGUUCAUCAUAAGGAAGGACAAGAACUAACUGCUUUGCUGAAUACUCCACAUAUUCAGGCACUUUUACUGGCCCACGAUAAGGUUGCUGAGCAGGAAAUGCAGCUAGAGCCCAUUACAGAUGAGAGAGUUUAUGAAAGUAUUGGCCAGUAUGGAGGAGAAACUGUAAAAAUAGUUCGUAUAGAAAAGGCUCGUGAUAUUCCGUUGGGUGCUACAGUUCGUAAUGAAAUGGACUCUGUCAUCAUUAGCCGGAUAGUAAAAGGGGGUGCUGCAGAGAAAAGUGGUCUGUUGCAUGAAGGAGAUGAAGUUCUAGAGAUUAAUGGCAUUGAAAUUCGGGGGAAAGAUGUCAAUGAGGUUUUUGACUUGUUGUCUGAUAUGCAUGGUACUUUGACUUUUGUCCUGAUUCCCAGUCAACAGAUCAAGCCGCCUCCUGCCAAGGAAACAGUAAUCCAUGUAAAAGCUCAUUUUGACUAUGACCCCUCAGAUGACCCUUAUGUUCCAUGUCGAGAGUUAGGUCUGUCUUUUCAAAAAGGUGAUAUACUUCAUGUGAUCAGUCAAGAAGAUCCAAACUGGUGGCAGGCCUACAGGGAAGGGGACGAAGAUAAUCAACCUCUAGCCGGGCUUGUUCCAGGGAAAAGCUUUCAGCAGCAAAGGGAAGCCAUGAAACAAACCAUAGAAGAAGAUAAGGAGCCAGAAAAAUCAGGAAAACUGUGGUGUGCAAAGAAGAAUAAAAAGAAGAGGAAAAAGGUUUUAUAUAAUGCCAAUAAAAAUGAUGAUUAUGACAACGAGGAGAUCUUAACCUAUGAGGAAAUGUCACUUUAUCAUCAGCCAGCAAAUAGGAAGAGACCUAUCAUCUUGAUUGGUCCACAGAACUGUGGCCAGAAUGAAUUGCGUCAGAGGCUCAUGAACAAAGAAAAGGACCGCUUUGCAUCUGCAGUUCCUCAUACAACCCGGAGUAGGCGAGACCAAGAAGUAGCCGGUAGAGAUUACCACUUUGUUUCGCGGCAAGCAUUCGAGGCAGACAUAGCAGCUGGAAAGUUCAUUGAGCAUGGUGAAUUUGAGAAGAAUUUGUAUGGAACUAGCAUAGAUUCUGUACGGCAAGUGAUCAACUCUGGCAAAAUAUGUCUUUUAAGUCUUCGUACACAGUCAUUGAAGACUCUCCGGAAUUCAGAUUUGAAACCAUAUAUUAUCUUCAUUGCACCCCCUUCACAAGAAAGACUUCGGGCAUUAUUGGCCAAAGAAGGCAAGAAUCCAAAGCCUGAAGAGUUGAGAGAAAUCAUUGAGAAGACAAGAGAGAUGGAGCAGAACAAUGGCCACUACUUUGAUACGGCAAUUGUGAAUUCCGAUCUUGAUAAAGCCUAUCAGGAAUUGCUUAGGUUAAUUAACAAACUUGAUACUGAACCUCAGUGGGUACCAUCCACUUGGCUGAGGUGAAAGAAACAUCCAUUCUGUGGCAUGUUGGACUUGAUCUGGCAAAAACUGCCAAUAGGAGGACUGCCCGACACUGCAGCAAGAUUGAGGAUAAGAUGGAAGGCAGCAGUAUAAGCUGUAGAUCUGUUCUUAGAUCUCUUGAAUUAGUGAGACGACAGUUCCCUUAGGCAGUUUGUGCAUGGCAUCCUUUAUUCUCUAUACAUGGCUUUAGCGGUUCUUGCCUCAUUUUGGGAUUCUAAAUGGAAGCUUUCAACAGAGCAUUCCAUUUUGUCCUGUUAAAACCUUUUGUUUUCACCUAAACCCUUUCUGCUUAGUUGUAUCUCUGUGAAAAACUUGUAUACACAAGCGUCCAUGUCUCACACAAAUAUUGAUGUGAUUAUUCUUAAGUGUUAAAUCAUUAACACUUAAAUGACUUCAUUGGGAAUAUUGAGCAGAGGGACUGUGCUUCUAUGCACUGGGCAAGGCAGUAUUUGCUUAGGAAACUAAUUUAGUCAUCAGAGAUACUUUCCUAAAAAGGAAAAAUAAAAAACAAAAUGGUGCCACUUUGGGUUGAAGCUACUUUGUUAGGCUUGAAUUCAUUUAUAUGUCUUUUGAUUCUUAAAAAAACAAAAAACAUUCCAUUAGAAGCACCAGUUUUUUUGCUCAGACUUUGUGGAUCAGACUCUACACUCAACACACUCUAAUCUACUUAAAGGUAUACAAAAUAUGCUGAUCUUUUUUAAAUUAUGAUUUCCUGAAUUUUUUUCUUAAGUCGUCUCAACUGAUUUACUCACUUAGCUUCCCUUCCCUCAUCAGCAUAGUAUAAUAGAAUGUAUGUUACAUUUUUAUGAAUGGCAGGUGUUCAUUAUAAUCUGUAUUGACUUAAAAAGUUUCUUCCUCAUGAUGCUAAUAGUUUUUUGUAUACAUGGGAGGAUAGCACAUUUGACAGUUUUUGCAUUUUUAUGUAUGAGCACAGUAUCCUAUGACUGUGCUACGUAUAUAUAGGUAAUAAACUGGAAUUCUGUUGAUGAAUAUAGCUGCUGUACUGUAUAUUAAUAUUUAAUAGAUCAACAAAUGGUCAUUGAAAACACUUGUUUAGCAUUAGAAUAAAAUUAUAUAUGUCCUUGGGAAAUAUUAUGACAGUUGACUUUAAGAUCAAAAGGAAGGGAAGACCUGAAAGUCAUUUGAACAUUUUAGGAAAAGAAUAUUGGAGAGAAAAAGGUAUUAAAUAUAUAGAAAUAGGUUUUUAACCUAACAAGGUCUGCCUCUUAUGACGAGAAUGCAACAGCUUGGUAAAUCAUAAAAGAAACAUUUAAGCUAAUAGGAUUUUCGUACUGUCUCUAUAGCUGUAGCUUUAAAAUUCAACGUAUAUAAUUGGCAUGGAAACUUAAUUUGCAGUCUUUUCAAGCCUUUAGGAUAGUGUGAUGUGUAACAAACAACCUCAAAUGUGAAUGCCUUGAUUUUAUUUUUAUGGUGACUUUAGCUACAGCAUUUCCUAUACCCAGAGCUAAACACUGGAAUAAUACUGACAUCAUUUAAUUUAACAUAAGCAAUUAUGUUUAAGGAGUAAUUUGUGUCAUGUACAUAUUUGAUUGAUUUUUUUUCUUCUACAUAAUUUUAUUUGAACAAAUGUAGACAGUUUAUAUGUCGCCUUUUUCUGUUCAAAUUUGCAUGGCCUAUUAAGUUGGCUGGAGAGUGUUUUAUGUGGAAAUAUUUUCAAGAUAAUGUUCCUUAGGAAGAAAAUAACAUUCUUGGGUUGAGGGAAGGAAUGCCAUACACUACUGUCUCUUCAGAUCUGAAAUACUCCAGUUUAGAGCCAGGAAAUUUCACAGGUCACACCGAUUUUUAGCAUUAAAAACUAAGGAAUAUACUUAGCACUUACUUAAUCUUUUCAGUUUUCCAGUUUACGUCUCAGGAAUGAAGUGUAGUCUAUGGUUGACAAUGGAGUUUUGUGAUCCUGCUUAUUGUAACUGACAACUGUUUUCAACUCCAAGAGCUAAACUAUUGGCAGUUCAUGUUAAGUUAGAGUGAGGGUGUAGGUAGUGUCAGUGAGUGGCUCUUGUGCCUGCUGUAGACAUUAGGCCUGCACUAGGGCCAUGUGCUGUCAAGAUUCAGGAACAUGGCUUUAACAAGCAGAUCUUGUAUCAAGGCAGAGGUGAUGCCAUGCCAUACUUUUAGGAAGUCUGAGAUGAUAAAUAUUUCAAGGUCAGUGAAGUCUAUCAAUCAUUCUCCCCUUCCUCAUCAGCAAUGGUAGAUAGAAAUGUCCUAAACUUUUCUAAAUCCUAGUGAUGAGGAUGUGCUGAUAUUCAACAUAGUCCUUAAAGUGAAAACUGAGUUGUUGCUGACCUCCACAAAAGAAUAUGGAAAAAAGCCUUGCUGUACACCUAGUUGUACAGCCACUCUGGCCAAUUCCAUUUCCUGUCCCUCUGUGGUUCUGACUGGAGACCCCAGUGUGGGGGAGGUCUUACCAUUUAAUAUAGAAAUGAUAUCAAUAACUAAUGCUAUGUACUUGGAAAAUCCAAAUAAGGAAGUUUUAGGUUGGUGCAUAACUUUGUUUCUCAAAUUUUCGUUGUCAGAACAAAUGGAAGGAGAAUAUUAUUUAGACUAAUCCAGAUUUGCUUUCUAUGAAAAUCUAAUGUCUGGAUUAUCUUCCUUUUCUCAUGGCCUAAGAAAUAAGGAUCAAUAAGGAAUGAUUUGAAUGUAAUUUUGUGAAUGUGUGGAAAAUAUAAAGCAGGGAUUUAGCCUUAAUAAAGGUAACCUUCUGACAUCUGUUGUUAAUCCCCCUUUGUACUCUUUUCCUGUAUCUGCACUGUUAUUUUGAGAUGUCAUACUGUACACUGUAUUGUAAAAAUAAAAAGUAAAAUUAUAUUUCAAAUUUUAAAAGCCACUAAGCAAUUUCUCUUGCUAUUUGCUCGGCCACUCAAGGUUUCCACACAUGUAAAGACCACCCUCCUCUUCAAGUUUUUGCCAAAAGCAAGACCAUUGGAUCCUCCAGCUACAACACAAAAUACUUUUUGAUUUGUUCUUUACAGAGGGAUAGUGCCCCCUGUUGGCACAGGUAUAGGUAGGUCCUGUUUCCUUAAUUAUUAAAACCAACAACUAAGUGUAUUAAAGAUGGACAACGCAAGG